GUGACGCGGCCGCCGGCCCGGGGCUGGGUACAUUGUCGCGCGGCCGCUUCCCCCCGGCCGGGCCCCCGCCGCCCCGCGGUCCCCAGAGCGCCAGGCCCCCGGGGGGAGGGAGGGAGGGCGCCGGGCCGGUGGGAGCCAGCGGCGCGCGGUGGGACCCACGGAGCCCCGCGACCCGCCGAGCCUGGAGCCGGGCCGGGUCGGGGAAGCCGGCUCCAGCCCGGAGCGAACUUCGCAGCCCGUCGGGGGGCGGCGGGGAGGGGGCCCGGAGCCGGAGGAGGGGGCGGCCGCGGGCACCCCCGCCUGUGCCCCGGCGUCCCCGGGCACCAUGCUGUCCAACUCCCAGGGCCAGAGCCCGCCGGUGCCGUUCCCCGCCCCGGCCCCGCCGCCGCAGCCCCCCACCCCUGCCCUGCCGCACCCCCCGGCGCAGCCGCCGCCGCCGCCCCCGCAGCAGUUCCCGCAGUUCCACGUCAAGUCCGGCCUGCAGAUCAAGAAGAACGCCAUCAUCGAUGACUACAAGGUCACCAGCCAGGUCCUGGGGCUGGGCAUCAACGGCAAAGUUUUGCAGAUCUUCAACAAGAGGACCCAGGAGAAAUUCGCCCUCAAAAUGCUUCAGGACUGCCCCAAGGCCCGCAGGGAGGUGGAGCUGCACUGGCGGGCCUCCCAGUGCCCGCACAUCGUACGGAUCGUGGAUGUGUACGAGAAUCUGUACGCAGGGAGGAAGUGCCUGCUGAUUGUCAUGGAAUGUUUGGACGGUGGAGAACUCUUUAGCCGAAUCCAGGAUCGAGGAGACCAGGCAUUCACAGAAAGAGAAGCAUCCGAAAUCAUGAAGAGCAUCGGUGAGGCCAUCCAGUAUCUGCAUUCAAUCAACAUUGCCCAUCGGGAUGUCAAGCCUGAGAAUCUCUUAUACACCUCCAAAAGGCCCAACGCCAUCCUGAAACUCACUGACUUUGGCUUUGCCAAGGAAACCACCAGCCACAACUCUUUGACCACUCCUUGUUAUACACCGUACUAUGUGGCUCCAGAAGUGCUGGGUCCAGAGAAGUAUGACAAGUCCUGUGACAUGUGGUCCCUGGGUGUCAUCAUGUACAUCCUGCUGUGUGGGUAUCCCCCCUUCUACUCCAACCACGGCCUUGCCAUCUCUCCGGGCAUGAAGACUCGCAUCCGAAUGGGCCAGUAUGAAUUUCCCAACCCAGAAUGGUCAGAAGUAUCAGAGGAAGUGAAGAUGCUCAUUCGGAAUCUGCUGAAAACAGAGCCCACCCAGAGAAUGACCAUCACCGAGUUUAUGAACCACCCUUGGAUCAUGCAAUCAACAAAGGUCCCUCAAACCCCACUGCACACCAGCCGGGUCCUGAAGGAGGACAAGGAGCGGUGGGAGGAUGUCAAGGGGUGUCUUCAUGACAAGAACAGCGACCAGGCCACUUGGCUGACCAGGUUGUGAGCAGAGGAUUCUGUGUUCCUGUCCAAACUCAGUGCUGUUUCUUAGAAUCCUUUUAUUCCCUGGGUCUCUAAUGGGACCUUAAAGACCAUCUGGUAUCAUCUUCUCAUUUUGCAGAAGAGAAACUGAGGCCCAGAGGCGGAGGGCAGUCUGCUCAAGGUCACGCAGCUGGUGACUGGUUGGGGCAGACCGGACCCAGGUUUCCUGACUCCUGGCCCAAGUCUCUUCCUCCUAUCCUGCGGGAUCACUGGGGGGCUCUCAGGGAACAGCAGCAGUGCCAUAGCCAGGCUCUCUGCUGCCCAGCGCUGGGGUGAGGCUGCCGUUGUCAGCGUGGACCACUAACCAGCCCGUCUUCUCUCUCUGCUCCCACCCCUGCCGCCCUCACCCUGCCCUUGUUGUCUCUGUCUCUCACGUCUCUCUUCUGCUGUCUCUCCUACCUGUCUUCUGGCUCUCUCUGUACCCUUCCUGGUGCUGCCGUGCCCCCAGGAGGAGAUGACCAGUGCCUUGGCCACAAUGCGCGUUGACUACGAGCAGAUCAAGAUAAAAAAGAUUGAAGAUGCAUCCAACCCUCUGCUGCUGAAGAGGCGGAAGAAAGCUCGGGCCCUGGAGGCUGCGGCUCUGGCCCACUGAGCCACCGCGCCCUCCUGCCCACGGGAGGACAAGCAAUAACUCUCUACAGGAAUAUAUUUUUUAAACGAAGAGACAGAACUGUCCACAUCUGCCUCCUCUCCUCCUCAGCUGCAUGGAGCCUGGAACUGCAUCAGUGACUGAAUUCUGCCUUGGUUCUGGCCACCCCAGAGUGGGAGAGGCUGGGAGGUUGGGAGGCUGUGGAGAGAAGUGAGCAAGGUGCUCUUGAACCUGUGCUCAUUUUGCAAUUUUAUCAGUAAUUUGACUUAGAGUUUUUACGAAACCUCUUUUGUUGUCCUUGCCCCACUCCUCUCCACCAGACGCCUUCCUCUCUGGAUACUGCAAAGGCUUGUGGUUUGUUAGAGGGUAUUUGUGGAAACUGUCAUAGGGAUUGUCCCUGUGUUGUCCCAUCUGCCCUCCCUGUUUCUCCACAACAGCCUGGGGUUGUCCCCGCUGGCUCACGCGUUCUGGGAGCUCAAGGCCACCUUGGAGGAGGAUGCCACGCACUUCCUCUCUCGGAGCCCUCAGACAUCUCCAGUGUGCCAGACAAAUAGGAGUGAGUGUAUGUGUGUGUGUGUGUGUGUGUGUGUGCACACGUGUGUAUGAGUGCGCAGAUCUGUGCCUGGGAUCGUGCAUUUGAGGGGCCAGGGGCAGGCAGGGCUGCAGAGGGAGACGGCCCUGCUGGGGCUUAGGAACCUUCUCCCUUCUUGGGUCUGCCCUGCCCAUACUGAGCCUGCCAAAGUGCCUGGGAAGCCCACCCAGAUUCUGAAACAGGCCCUCUGUGGCCUGUCUCUAUUAGCUGGGUUCCGGGAGGCAGAGAGGAGUGACCGGGCACUGGCACUGCGAUCAGGAAGACUGGACCCCCAGCCCCCAGGGCCCCCCUCCCCCCACUUAGUGCUGGUCCUAGGUCCUCUGAGGCACUCAUCUACUGAAUGACCUCUCUACUUCCCCUUCUUGCCAUUAUUAACCCAUUUUUGUUUAUUUUCCUUAAAUUUUUAGCCAUUUCUCCAUGGGCCACCGCCCAGCUCAUGUAGGUGAGCCUGGGCAGCUUCUGUUGGCAGAGCUUUUGCAUUUCCUGUGUUUGUCCUGGGUUCUGGGGCAUCAGCCAGCUACCCCUUGUGGGCAAAGGCAGGGCCACUUUUGAAGUCUUCCCUCAGAUUUCCAUUGUGUGGCCUGGUGGGUCAGGGGGAGUCUUUGCACCAAAGAUGUCCUGACUUUGCCCCCUUGCCCAUCAGCCAUUUGCCAUCACCCCAAACAACUCAGCUUCGGGGCCGGUGAGGGGAGGGGCCUCCCCCAGCACAGAUGAGGAGCAGCUGGGGUAGGCUGUCUGUGCCAUGGCCCCCCACUCCCCCUUCCCUUGGAGGGAGAGGUGGCAGGAAUACUUCACCUUUCCUCUCCCUCAGGGGCAGGUGGUGGAGGGGCGCCCAGGGUCGUCUUUGUGUAUGGGGGAAGGCGCUGGGUGCCUGCAGCGCCUCCCUUGUCUCAGAUGGUGUGUCCAGCACUCGAUUGUUGUAAACUGUUGUUUUGUAUGAGCGAAAUUGUCUUUACUAAACAGAUUUAAUAGUU